CAAAAUUGGAGAGAAACCCAGGCGUCCUGCCUCCUGUCUCUUCAGGUUCUUGAGCUAACACAUUUCAAGUGGCCCGGAAACUGAGGAGGCAGGGGUGGUUAAGCUAUGGGAGAAAGGAUGGCCUAGUUGGGGGAUGAGGGCCAGGUCUGAGAAUCUACUCUUGGGUUUAUUGCCCAGGCCUGGCCUCUGGUGGGCUGUGUGAGUUUGGGCUUCCUGUGUGGCCUUAGUCUGCCUGUCUGUGGAUUGGGGAGACUUGGUGGCUGGGUGGGGACUGUCUUUCUGGAGACACAGGCUCAGUCCAGACUGGCAUGUGAAGGCUGUGUGUGCUGUUCUUGGAGCAUAUGGAUGUGGCCCGUGAGAGCUCGUGCAUGGGGUGAGGGCCUGUUGCGGGCAUCUGAAUCUGCCUGGGGCUGCUGGGUUCCAGCCCUUGAUAGGCAUGUUAGGGCGAGCUGAGGGUGAAAGCCUGCUAGGCAGGAUGAGGCACACGUGUGUGCAGGCACACACAGGCUCUGACUUGGCAUCUUCAGAGACUGUGCAGUCUGGGACCCUCCUUUUGCCUGCAUUGUGAGGACAGGGCUCUGGGGAGAGAAUUAAAUGACACAUGUUGGCACAGGGUCUUCUUUUGUCUCUUCCCCCCAAAGAAACAAAAUAGGUUUUGUAUCUAAGUUGGGGAGGAGAUCUAGAUACAGCCAAUCUAGCUACCCUUCCAAAUGCAGUCGAGUUUUAGGGACCCAAGGAAGCAAAUGUGAUUGGAGUCAGAUGAACUUUUGGGCCUGUGCCUCAGUUUCCCCUCCUAUCUGGUGAGAAGGGGAAACAGAGUUGCAGGGGUACCUGGCUCAUACCCAACUAUGAAUUUAACACUUUUUCCAGUCAGAAAACAGUAUUCCAGGAACUGUUUGCUGUUAGGUGAGGUGAGAGAGAGGACAUGUGCACAUCACAGAUACACACUAGUGAGACCCCUGUCUAGUGACCACUUGCCCCUAGACUGAGGAACAUAGGCUUCUUCCCAGACCACCUACUUCUCAAUUGUAGGUAGAGUGGGAUGCAAAGGAGGCUCAUCUGCCUGCUUCCCCGACUCCCAAGUCUCAGAAGAGAAAAGGGGUUGAGGCUUUGGGUUUCUGGUUUGGAGACAAUACUGUCUACCCUUGGGGGCGGGGGUGGGGGCUGGGCUGAUAAGGGAGUGGCCGUUAGUGGGGAGGCAGAAGGCCCAACUGGUUAUCUGGUAGGCCACACCCAACAGGCACCCACCCCCAUUUAUCUUUCCAUCCCUUGCCCUCCUGAGACCCUGAGGGUGGAGGAAGGGCAGAGUUUGAAAAUCCUCCCUUUUCCUCCCCCACUUUGGUCUCUAGAGGGCAAUAGAGGGGUCAGAUGGUAGAAAGAGUAUAGGAUGUGGGAAUCAGAAGAUCCAAGCUCAAGUCCUAGCUUUGACAGUUACUAGCUUUAUGAUCUUGGCAAGGUCCUUUGAGCCCUCAGUUGCCUCAUCUGUAAAAUGGGAAUGUUAUGGUCAGCCCUGCUACCUCAUAAGGUUGUUUUGAUGAUUGAGUGAAAGUAUGUAGAUUAAAAGGGGGUUUAUCAAUAUUAGAUUCUAAUGAUUGGAUAUUUAUUUAUUCUGUAAUCAUUCUUCCCAGCUUCAAUUCCUCUUCUGUCAUCUAGGACUCAGCCAAAUGAAGAAAUGGGAUCUUGGGUUGUUCCUCAAAGUCAUUCAAGCUGUACUCGCCGAAGGAGCCCCCGAACGGCAACGCCUUUCCCCCCUUCCAUCCCGGCACCAUGCUGGAUAGGGAUGUGGGCCCAACUCCCAUGUAUCCGCCUACAUACCUGGAGCCAGGGAUUGGGAGGCACACACCAUAUGGCAACCAAACUGACUACAGAAUAUUUGAGCUUAACAAACGGCUUCAGAACUGGACAGAGGAGUGUGACAAUCUCUGGUGGGAUGCAUUCACGACUGAGUUCUUUGAGGAUGAUGCCAUGUUGACCAUCACUUUCUGCCUGGAGGAUGGACCAAAGAGAUAUACCAUUGGCCGGACCCUGAUCCCACGCUACUUCCGCAGCAUCUUUGAGGGGGGUGCUACGGAGCUGUACUAUGUUCUUAAGCACCCCAAGGAGGCAUUCCACAGCAACUUUGUGUCCCUCGACUGUGACCAGGGCAGCAUGGUGACCCAGCAUGGCAAGCCCAUGUUCACCCAGGUGUGUGUGGAGGGCCGGUUGUACCUGGAGUUCAUGUUUGACGACAUGAUGCGGAUAAAGACGUGGCACUUCAGCAUCCGGCAGCACCGAGAGCUCAUCCCCCGCAGCAUCCUUGCCAUGCAUGCCCAAGACCCCCAGAUGUUGGAUCAGCUCUCCAAAAACAUCACUCGGUGUGGGCUGUCCAAUUCCACUCUCAACUACCUCCGACUCUGUGUGAUACUCGAGCCCAUGCAAGAGCUCAUGUCACGCCACAAGACCUACAGCCUCAGCCCCCGCGACUGCCUCAAGACCUGCCUUUUCCAGAAGUGGCAGCGCAUGGUAGCACCCCCUGCGGAGCCCACACGUCAGCAGCCCAGCAAACGGCGGAAACGGAAGAUGUCAGGGGGCAGCACCAUGAGCUCUGGUGGUGGCAACACCAACAACAGCAACAGCAAGAAGAAGAGCCCAGCUAGCACCUUCGCCCUCUCCAGCCAGGUACCUGAUGUGAUGGUGGUGGGGGAGCCCACCCUGAUGGGCGGGGAGUUCGGGGACGAGGACGAGAGGCUCAUCACCCGGCUGGAGAACACCCAGUUUGACGCAGCCAACGGCAUUGACGACGAGGACAGCUUUAACAACUCCCCUGCACUGGGCGCCAACAGCCCCUGGAACAGCAAGCCUCCGUCCAGCCAAGAAAGCAAAUCGGAGAACCCCACGUCACAGGCCUCCCAGUAAAAGGCCCUGCUGUGGCCACCCAGUGCUCUGCCUACCUGCCCCACCCCUCACAGCCCCAGGGAGCAGAAGACAGAAUGAAGAGACUGAGCAUCUAAAAUGGGCAGCCUCCAUCCACCCGCUUCAGGGAGGAACUGGACUCUCUGGGGGCAGGUGCCAAGAUUUGCCCCCCCAGUGGCCCUGGGCUGGGCCUGGCCUCUACAGAGCCUUUUAGGGGGAGGGGGUACUCAUGUGGAUGCCUACUUGGAACCUGGGCCUCUGAGACAUGUCCUGACCACCCCCCAGGGCAUUUGCCUCCAUCUUCACCCCAGAUUGUGGGUUUCCCAUCCCCCUGACUUUACCCCUUUCAAGCCUGGGGUUGUCUAUACCCACAGCCCUUAGGGACUUAAAGUUACGGGGCUUCGUUGAAUGCUCCUUCCCCUAGGCAGCUGGUAAUAGAGGGGUAAAGCUCUGGGCCCCUCCUCCCUGCUGCCACUUAUCCCAGCUCCAAGUUUUUUUAAAAAUAAUAUUAUUAAAAAUGUAAGUUAAAAAAAAAAUCACUCAUGUCCCCCCCUCUUCCCCCUAUUAAAAGUCCAGCUACCUCCCUACUCUUGGCAGAUGGGGGCCUAGGGCCUAGGUGGGGGUGAGAGUGGGGGAGGGAGGUGUGCAUACCAUUUUAUAUGGUGUGAGAGCUUCAGACCAAGGAGACAUUUCACCAUCUCUCCCCCUUUCCUCUGGGGUGACUGCAGUUGAGGAAAGCAUGCCAUGGGGUAGGGGGACAUUGGUGGCCACAUUUUGGUGACAGACCCCUGCUGUUGUCUCUGUGUCCCCAUUCUCUGGACUCUGGCCUGCCCUCCUAGUGCUUGUGACUCCCUCUCUUCCAGCCCCACCCCCAUGGUAUGUAUAUUCCUUACAAGUCCUCCACAAGAGCAGCUGUCUAGGAUGCGGGGAGGGGAGGCUCCUUCCCUUAGGGAGCGUGGAGAGAAGGGAGCAGCCUUGUUGCUGUAUUUUUGGUUUUGUUUCAGUUGGGCAGGCAUGGGAUGGGAGAGGGGCUCAGCCACUUUCCUCCAGAAUCUUCCCUCAGCCCCUCCAACUGCAUAUGUAAUCCUACUCUGUCCUUCAUAGAGGGGAAGGAGCCACAGAUGACAUCCCAGUUCUAAGCCCACCAGGGAGGAACAGGCCUCUGUCCCCAUAGGUGAGGUAGAGGUAGAGGGUCUUCACCUGCCAGUAUCCCCUGCCGCUCCUUCCUCACAGAAGGAAGGAGGAGGAGGCAGCCGGGAUCCUCGGCUCUGCCAGGGUGCAGCCAGGAGCAGGGUUUCACGCAGCUGGUCCAGCUCUGUGGCUUUGCUGCCUUUUCCUGUGGCCAGUCCCAGGAAGUGCUAACACCACCUCUCUCCCCACUCUUCCCUCUGGAUUCUGGGGUCCCCCACACCGUAUUUCCUCCACUCCAGCUGCCACUUUUGGAAGGGUAUUGAGUCAGGAGCUGAGGGAAGGGGUGAGGAAGGUGGACAUCCCAUCCCAACUGUAAUGCCUUUUUUUUUUUUUUUUUUUUUUUUUUUUUUUUUUUUUUUUUUUGGGCCAUUUGAGUCAUGUAUGGUACCAAUCAAUAAAGAGACUUUUCGGUUUGA